GAGGUAGCGAGGUCAGGGGUCAAGAGUGGAACACCCUCACUGGCCCGGGCCGGCGCGGGAGGGCUGUGUGAUGGCCUCGGAGCGCCCGGAGCCGGAGGUGGAAGAAGCUGGGCAGGUGUUCCUGUUAAUGAAAAAGGAUUAUCGAAUCUCCCGAAAUGUUCGCCUGGCUUGGUUCCUCAGUCAUCUGCACCAAACUGUGCAGGCCACACCCCAGGAGAUGCUGCUUCAGUCUGAACAGGAAUUGGAAGUCCUCAGUGUCCUGCCCCCUGGGUGGCAGCCAGAUGAACCAGUGGUCCCAAGGCCAUUCCUCCUGGUACCUUCCACCCGGGUCACCUUCCUGGCUUGGCAGUAUCGGUUUGUCAUUGAGUUGGACCUUAGCCCAUCUACUGGCAUUGUGGAUGAUUCCACAGGGGAGAUCUUGUUUGAUGAAGUUUUCCAUGCCCUGUCCCGCUGCUUAGGCGGGCUGCUUCGGCCCUUCCGAGUGCCUGGAUCUUGCAUCGACUUCCAGCCUGAGAUCUAUGUAACUAUCCAGGCCUACUCCUCCAUCAUUGGACUGCAGUCCCACCAGGUGCUGGUACAGGGCUGCCUCUUGGACCCUUCCCAGCGGGAGGUGUUCCUGCAGCAGAUAUAUGAGCAGCUCUGCCUCUUUGAGGAUAAGGUGGCCACCAUGCUGCAGCAGCAGUACGAUCCCCAGAGCCAGGCAGAAGACCAGUCCCCAGACUCAGGGGACCUACUGGGCCGGAAGGUAGGCGUCUCCAUGGUGACAGCUGAUCUUGGGCUGGUCAGUAUGAUUCGUCAGGGCAUCUUGGCACUGCAGUUACUACCCUCGAACUCUAGUGCAGGGAUUAUCGUGAUCACGGAUGGGGUGACCAGUGUACCUGAUGUUGCUGUCUGUGAGACACUGCUGAACCAGCUUCGCAGUGGCACUGUGGCUUGUUCCUUUGUCCAGGUGGGAGGAGUUUACUCUUAUGACUGCAGUUUUGGCCAUGUGCCCAAUGUGGAAUUAAUGAAGUUCAUCGCAAUGGCAACAUUUGGGUCCUACCUGUCCACUUGUCCUGAGCCGGAGCCAGGCAACCUGGGUCUGACUGUCUACCACCGGGCAUUUCUCCUCUAUUCCUUCCUGCGCAGUGGGGAAGCACUGAACCCUGAAUAUUACUGCGGCUCUCAGCACCGCCUAUUUAAUGAGCACCUGGUCUCUGCAAGCAGCAACCCUGCCCUGGCCUUGCGCCGGAAGAAGCACACUGAGAAGGAGGUGCCAGCCGACUUGGUCAGCACUGUGUCCGUACGGCUUCGAGAGGGCUACAGUGUCCGAGAGGUCACACUGGCCAAAGGAGGGUCCCAAUUGGAGGUAAAGCUGGUGCUGCUGUGGAAACACAACAUGCGCAUUGAGUAUGUGGCUAUGGCACCCUGGCCCCUGGAGCCUGAGGGCCCUCGAGUAACACGGGUGGAAGUGACGAUGGAAGGCGGCUACGACAUUUUGCAUGAUGUGUCCUGUGCACUAAGGCAGCCCAUUCGUUCAUUGUAUCGUACCCAUGUUAUCCGGCGUUUCUGGAACACGCUGCAGAGCAUCAACCAGACAGACCAGAUGCUUGCCCACCUUCAGUCCUUCUCCUCAGUGCCUGAGCAUUUCACGCUUCCUGACAGCACCAAGAGCGGAGUGCCACUCUUCUACAUCCCUCCAGGCUCCACCACCCCGGUGCUCUCCCUCCAGCCCAGUGGUUCUGACUCAUCCCAUGCCCAGUUUGCUGCCUACUGGAAGCCAGUGCUGUCCAUGGAUGCAAAUUCCUGGCAGCGAUGGCUGCACAUGCAUCGCCUGGUGCUAAUCCUGGAGCAUGACACACCAAUCCCCAAGCACUUGCACACCCCGGGCAGCAAUGGGCGCUACAGCACUAUCCAGUGCAGGAUCUCCCACUCCUCCCUGACCUCUCUGCUGCGGGACUGGAGCAGCUUCGUACUAGUCGAGGGCUAUUCUUAUGUUAAGCUGCUCUCCAGUGCCCCAGACCAGCCCCCCAAUUCCUUCUACAUGGUCCGUAUCAUUUCCAAGGCCCCAUGCAUGGUUCUUCGCCUGGGUUUUCCCAUUGGCACACCAGCACCGGCCCGGCACAAGAUUGUGUCAGGCUUGAGGGAAGAGAUCCUGCGGCUGCGUUUCCCCCACCGGGUACAAAGCAAGGAGCCAACGCCCAAGGUGAAACGAAAAGGGCUAGGGGGUGCUGGUGGGGGCAGCUCUCCCUCCAAGUCACCCCCCGUGCUGGGGCCACAGCAGGCCCUGUCUGACCGGCCCUGCCUUGUGGUCCUGCAUAAGCCACUGGACAAACUGCUCAUCAGGUAUGAGAAGCUGCCCUUGGACUACCGGGCACCCUUCUUGCUGACAUUGGAGCCACCAGGUCCACUGCCCUUGGUGUCAGGCCGCUCAGCCUCUUCUAGCCUGGCGUCACUGUCCCGCUACCUCUACCAUCAGCGCUGGCUUUGGAGUGUCCCGUCAGGACUGGCCCCUGCGCUGCCUCUCAGUGCCAUUGCCCAGCUCCUCUCCAUCCUCACUGAAGUCCGACUUUCUGAAGGAUUCCACUUCGCCUGCAGUGGGGAAGGAAUCAUCAACAUGGUUCUGGAGCUUCCAAUUCAGAAUGAACCACCAGGGCAGGCUGCAGCUGAAGAGAAGCACACCUGUGUUGUCCAGUACAUCCUCUUCCCCCCACACUCUACCUCCACCAAAGACAGCUUCUCGACAGAUGAUGACAAUGAUGUGGAAGUGGAGGCCCUGGAGGGAGACUCAGAGCUCAAUCUGGUCACUGAGGUGUGGGUGGAGCCACAGUAUGGGCGAGUGGGACCUGGCCCUGGAAUCUGGAAGCACCUCCAGGACCUGACGUAUUCUGAGAUCCCGCAAGCUCUCCACCCACGGGAUGCUGCCUGCAUAGGCUCCAUGCUGAGCUUUGAAUACCUGAUACAGCUGUGUCAGAGCAAGGAAUGGGGUCCUCUGCCCCCAGAGCCGAGGGUCUCUGAUGGAUUGGAUCAGGGAGGAGACACCUGCGUCCAUGAGAUCCCUUUCCAUUUUGACCUAAUGGGAUUGCUGCCACAGUGCCAGCAGCUCCAGAUGUUCUUCCUCUUGCUUGCCAGAGAGCCAGAGGGUGUCCCUUUCGCCGAGGGGUCCUGUCCUGCCAACGACAUGGUGCUGUGCCUGCUGCACAGCUGCCUGGGGCAGGAGCUGAGUGACCGGGAGAUCCCACUGACCCCCGUUGACCAGGCUGCCUUCUUGAGUGAGGUGCUGCGGCGGACCUGCCACGUUCCAGGUGCCGAGGGGCCACUGCUGGGGGUUCAUGGGAUCCCGAAGGAGCAAGCAGUCGGCAGCACCCAGGCCACAGGAGACUCCGCUUUUACUUCCCUGAGUGUAGGUCUUCCUGAAACUCUCAAGCCUCUCAUCUCUGCCCAGCCCCCUCAGUGGCGCUGCUAUGCAAGGCUUGUGAACCCCCAGCAUGUGUUUCUGACUUUUCUCCCAGCUACCUUCUCAGAUGUCCAGCGUCUGGCUGCCUGUGGCCUGGAGGGACCCCCUCAAGAGGAGACAAAGCCUAAGUUUGGGGAUUGGAGUGGGGCUCCCAGUCUGAAAGAUCUAGGAGGAACUGGGAUCAAAGCUACAAAGUCCCACGUCCCUGUCCUCAGUGUGACCCUGGCUAGUGACAAUGCCCAGAAUCAAGGAGAGCUAAGUCCACCAUUCCGUCGAGACUUACAGGCUUACGCUGGGCGUCAGGCUUCCCAGACAGAGAGUGCGGAUGGGCCCCGGACCCGGUGUCCUGUCUACAUCUACAGCUGUUCACUGGAAGCGCUGAGGGAACAAAUGGUUGGCAUGCAGCCCCCUCAGGCGCCCCGAGACCUCAUCUUCCGGACUCAGUUCCUCGACCACCCCUCCCCAUCCUCAGCCUGGAUGGAACCCCGGUACAAGGAGGCAGCUAACCACUGUGCCCUGCUGCAGGAGCAUGCACAGCGGUGCUAUGUCCGUGGGCUAUUCCGCAGCUUGCAGCAAGCACAGAGUGUGACCUCCCAGGAUUUGCUGACAGCGGUAGAUGCCUGUGAGGAGCUACUACAAGAAAUAGACAUCACCCCAUUUCUCCUUGCAUUGUGUGGCCACACUUGGGGUUUGCCUCAUGCACCCCCAAGUCCUGGUCCUCUCAGCCCUGGGCCCUUCAGCAGCAGCAUGGAGGAGGGUGCUGAACCUCGGGAACGAGCUAUCCUAGCUUCUGAAUCCAGCAUAGAGACCGAGGACCUAAGCGAGCCUGAGUUUCAGAGCACCCGUGUCCCUGGCAUUCCAGACCCUGGGCCAGAGAUCUCUCUGACAGAUGUCUGCCAGCUCAGAGGAGAGGCCCAUGGUGCCCUUCAUAGCGUCAUCCAGGAGAAGUUCCUAGAGAUCAGUCGUCUCCACUUCCGCACAGUGCCUUCCAAUCCCCACUACUUCUUCUAUUGCCCUCCAUCCAGCAGGCGAGAAGAUGAGGGGCCUCGGGACACAGUAGACAGAAAAAUCAGUGACCUGGAGUUUUCAGAGGCUGAGCUUAUGGGAGAAGAAGGAGACACAUCUGCCUGCUGUGUGGUCACUGAGAGUGACCCAGAGCUAGAGGUAGAAUACCGGGAGAGCCGUGAAUCAGACCUGGGGCCUGCUGGGCUAGACUCUGCCUCGCUGUCAGACGUAGACACUGUGAAUCCUGAUGAAGACUCCUUCAGUAUCUUGGGGGGCGACUCACCCACUGGGCCUGAGAGCUUCCUUCAUGACCUGCCACCGCUCUUCCUGCACCUCACGUGCUCCGUGCGGCUACGUGGGCAGCACAGCUCAGUACCUGUGUGCAGCCUGCCUACCUGCCUGGGCCAGGUGCUUUCCAGUCUGGAGGGCCCCCCAGUUGGAGGCCGAGUUCCCUUGAGGGACCUCAGUGUGACUCUGGAUGUCUUCAUGCUGACUUUGCCCCUGGAAGUGGAGCUCCCCACGGCCUCGGACCCUCAGCACCACCGGUCAACAUCUGAAAGCAGUGCUUCAUUUCCACGAUCCCCAGGGCAGCCAUCAUCUUUAAGGUCAGAUGAUGGCCUCGGGCCCCCACUGCCACCCCCAGAAGAGGAGAGGCACCCAGGACUAUCCAAUUUGGCCACGCCCCACAGACUGGCUAUUGAGACCACCAUGAAUGAGAUCCGCUGGUUGUUGGAAGAUGAGAUGGUGGGGGCACUCCGAAGAGGGGGCAUCCCACAGAGUCCUGCCCUGCACCGCGCAGCUGCCCAUAUCCAUAGUUCUCCUGGACGCUCCACCUGCCUUCGCCAAACUCUGCCACUGAGUUUUGUAUUUGGGCCAGAGCGUUCCCUCACACAAUUCAAGGAGGAGUUCCGCCGCCUCCAUCUCCCUGGCCAUGUUCUUCUUGAAGACCCUGACAGUGGCUUCUUCUUUGUGGCAGCUGGCCAACAGCCAGGUGGGUCCCAUGGGGAGCCUUCUUCAGCGGCCUGGGCUUGGCACAGUCAUGAGGACAGGGCUGAAGGCAUCGAAGGGGAGACCCUGACAGCCAGCCCCCAAGCACCUGGGUCCCCAGAGGAUUCUGAGGGUGUCCCCCUCAUCAGCCUGCCCCGCGUGCCACAGGGAGGGAGUCAGCCUGGGCCCAGCCGGGGAUUAAGUCUCAUGUCCAGUCAGGGCAGUGUGGACUCAGACCACCUAGGUUAUGAUGGUGGCAGCAGUGGCUCAGACAGUGAGGGUCCCAAUGACACCCUUGGUGAGAAGGCCCCCUUCACAUUGCGGACUCCACCUGGGCCAGCACCUCCACAGCCUUCACUCUCAGGCCUCCCUGGGCCCUGCCUGCCUGACUUCUGGCUCAUUGUCCGGGUCCUGCAGGACCGUGUGGAAGUGUAUGCACAUGCACGGAGCCUGAUUCGGGAGGAUGGGGGGCCGGGCACUGAGUGUCGCCACCUGCAGCAGCUCCUGGUGAGGCGAGUUGGGGAGAUCUGCAGGGAGGUCAACCAGCGACUGCUUCUUCAAGACCUUCAUGACAGCCACGUGUGUAACUCUCUUCUGGUGGCCGAGAGUGAAGAAGAUCUGUGGCGCAGUGAGACUCCCUUCCACUCCCGUCAGCGGGCACCACUGCCCAGUGAUGAUUAUGCUGCUGAUGAGAGCUGUGCGCCCCGUGGGUACCUGGCAGCCACAAUGCAGUUUGUCCCUGGCCAUUUCUCCUGUGACGUUGUGUGGGGAACUGUGAUCCGAGUCCAUUCACGCCUCAAAAUGGGGCCCAGCAUGGGGGUCUCUCGGGCCAUCCAGGCCCUGCGCUCUGUGCUCAAUGCCUUCUCUGUGGUGAACCGGAAAAACAUGUUUGUUUACCAGGAGCGAGCAACAAAGGCUGUGUACUAUCUUCGGCUCCUAGAGACAUCCUGCAGUGACCGGCCAUGGAAAGGGGAUGCGCUGCCCCCUUCCCUCGCUCUGUCCCGAAGCCAAGAGCCCAUCUACUCUGAGGAAGCCUCGGGUCCUCGUUCUCCCUUAGACAUGGUCUCUAGCCGCAGUUCAGAUGCUGCUCGUCCUGUGGGCCAAGUGGACAGACAUAUCCAGCUGCUGGUCCAUGGUGUUGGGCAGGCAGGUCCUGAGAUCACGGAUGAGCUCGUGCGAGUUCUAUGUCGGCGCCUGGAUGAGGCCACGCUGGACGUCAUCACAGUUAUGCUUGUUCGGAACUGCAAGCUGACACCAGCUGAUGUGGAGUUCAUCCAGCCCCCUGGAAGUCUCCCCUCAGAGGUGCUGCAUCUGGCCCUACCCACCUCCUGCAGGCCCUGGCUUCCAGCCCUGGCAUGGUACCUACGGCAGAACUUGCUCAUCUUCCUGCACUCUCCCAAGUACACAGAUAGCAACAGCCGGAACCACUUCCAACAUCCACUCCCACCACAGGGUGGCCUCCCUGACUUGGACAUCUACUUGUAUAACAAGCCUGGUGGACAGGGCACUGGGGGCAAAGGGGUUGCCUGCAUCACUCUAGCCUUUGUGGAUGAAGGAGGGGCCCCCUUGUCACUGGCGUUGUGGCCCCCCUCCUCUCCGGGGCCCCCAGACCCACUGCGAGAGGAGGAAUUUGAGCAACUGACCCAGGUCAUCCGCUGCCCGGUUGUUGUGGACAGUUCUUCAGCUCAGAAUGGGGCCCCACGGCUUCGAUUGGAUGUGUGGGAAAAGGGGAACAUUAGUAUUGUGCAGCUGGAGGAGAAACUCCGAGGAGCAGCUCGCCAGGCCCUGGCCGAUGCCAUCAUCGAGCUUCAGCUGCUGCCAGCUUCACUAUGUACAGAGGACACACCCACAGGAAGUCUCAGGAACGGAUCGUUGGAAACUAAGAGCUCUGCAGGCCGAGCUAGCACCUUUCCCCCUGCCCCUGUCCCUGGGGAGCCUGUGACUCCACCCAGCAAAGCGGGCCGGCGUAGCUUCUGGGAUAUGCUGAGUAAAACAGAAUGUGGGGAUUUGGGUUCCCCCAAAACAACUGAUGACAUUGUCCUGGAUCGGCCAGAAGACACUCGGGGCCGGAGGCGUCACAAAACCGAGAGUGUUCGGACUCCUGGUGGAGCUGAGCGGGCGCCAGGCUCAGAUUCUGGAGCCCAGAGACAAAAGCGCCGGACAACACAGCUAGAAGAGGGUGAGGUGGGGACCCUUCAUCCUGUGUUUGCCCGUGUUGCUCAGCGCUGGAUGGAGUUUAUGGUUCAGAUUGGUUGUGCCUCAGUGUCCAGAAGCUCUGCCCACAUGGUGUCCCGGUUCCUCCUUCCAUCCAUCCUGUCUGAGUUCACCGCACUGGUCACCUCAAUGGCUGGAGACACCAGUGUCCGCAUCUUUGAGCAGCAUUUGGGUUCAGAGCCAGAGAUCUUCGGCCCUUGUUCCCCUGGGCAACUGGGCCCCUCUCCCCGCCCUGCAGCUGAGCGGCAUCUGCUGCUUCUGGGAAGGAACUUCUUGCAGUGGAGGAGACCAACACAGCAGGCUGCCAAAGCCAUGCAGCGCUUCGAGCCAGGAGGUGAUGGGAGCUCAGGGCGAAAUGCUCCCCGGCAGAGGCUCUUGCUACUAGAGGUUGUGGACAAGAAGCUACAGCUGCUGACCUACAACUGGGCUCCAGACCUGGGGGCAGCAUUGGGCCGAGCGCUGGUUCGCCUGGUGCAGUGGCAGAAUGCACGAGCCCAUCUCAUCUUCUGCCUACUCAGCCAGAAGCUUGGCCUCUUCCAUCAUUAUGGCCAGUUGGACUUCCCCGUGCGAGAUGAAAAGGAGCCAAACCCAUUCCUGCUGCCGACCAUGGAAGUGGAGACCCUCAUCCGGAGUGCAAGUCCCCCGCUGAGCCGUGAGCAGGGCCGACUGAGUGGGUCCUCUCGUGGUGGGGGUCCUCUUCCCCUGGACACAUUCCCCUUUGACGAGGCCCUAAGGGAUAUCACGGCUGCCCGCCCCAGCUCCGUACUUGGUCCUGUGCCCAGACCUCCUGAUCCUGUCACCUACCAUGGACAACAGUUCCUAGAGAUCAAGAUGGCAGAGCGCAGAGAGCUGGAGCGCCAGAUGAAGAUGGAAAACCUGUUUGUAACCUGGCAGCAGCGUUCUACCCCAGCCACCAUGCCCAUCAGUGCUGGAGAGCUGGAGACCCUGAAGCAGUCAUCCCGCCUGGUGCAUUACUGUGCAACAGCCAUGCUCUUCGACCCAGCUGCCUGGCUGCAUGGGCCCCCAGAGACCUCUGGACCCCCUGACGGGCAGCGGCGCCAUCGCCCUGAGUCAGGGUCUGGGAGCCGAGAGGCCCCCACAAGCUGUGAAUCCUUGGAUGUGUCGCCCCCGGGAGCCCGUGAGGAGCCUUGGCUGAAGGAGCUGAGCUUGGCUUUCCUGCAGCAAUAUGUGCAGUAUCUGCAGAGCAUAGGUUUUGUGCUGGUACCACUGCGGCCCCCCUCACCCGCCCGCAGCACCAGCCGGCCACGGGCCAUGGCUAUCCUUGGAACAGAGGGUCGAGGCUCCUUCUCCUGCCCUAAAACCAAGACUGAUGGGAGCCCCAAGAGCACUAGCUCUCCGGUAACCACCUACCACCUGCAGCGGGCACUGCCUGGGGGCAUCAUCCUCAUGGAACUGGCAUUCCAGGGCUGUUACUUCUGUGUCAAACAGUUUGCCCUGGAAUGUUCCCGAAUCCCAAUGGGGCAGGCUGUCAACUCACAGCUGUCCAUGCUGUUCACAGAGGAGUGUGACAAGGUGCGGGACCUGAUGCACGUGCACUCGUUCAGCUAUGACUUCCAUCUGCGCCUCGUGCAUCAGCACGUGCUAGGUGCCCAUCUGGUGCUGCGGCACGGCUACCACCUCACCACCUUUCUGCGACACUUCCUGGCCCACCACCCUGACGGACCCCACUUUGGCCGCAAUCACAUUUACCAAGGGACAUUGGAGCUCCCCACACCACUCAUUGCUGCCCACCAGCUAUACAACUACGUGGCUGAUCACGCCAGCUCUUACCACAUGAAGCCAUUGCGAAUGGCCCGGCCAGGGGGCCCAGAACACAACGAGUAUGCCCUGGUGUCGGCAUGGCACAGUUCUGGCUCCUACCUGGACUCUGAGGGACUUCGACACCAGGAUGACUUUGAUGUGUCUCUGCUUGUCUGUCACUGUGCUGCACCCUUUGAGGAGCAAGGAGAGGCUGAGCGGCACGUUCUGCGGCUACAGUUCUUCGUGGUGCUCACCAGCCAGCGAGAGCUCUUCCCCAGGCUCACUGCUGACAUGCGCCGCUUCCGGAAGCCACCCAGACUGCCCCCUGAGCCAGAGGCUCCUGGGAGUUCAGCUGGCAGCCCUGGGGAGGCCUCAGGGCUUAUUCUAGCGCCUGGACCGGCUCCUCUGUUCCCACCACUGGCUGCAGAGGUGGGCAUGGCACGAGCACGGCUGGCUCAGCUGGUGCGGCUGGCUGGAGGGCACUGCCGUCGGGACACCCUUUGGAAGCGCCUCUUCUUGCUGGAGCCACCGGGGCCUGAUCGACUGCGGCUAGGGGGGCGCCUGGCCCUGGCAGAGCUGGAGGAACUCCUAGAAGCAGUCCAUGCCAAAUCCAUUGGGGACAUCGACCCCCAGCUGGACUGCUUCCUAUCCAUGACGGUCUCCUGGUACCAGAGCCUGAUCAAAGUUCUCCUAAGCCGCUUCCCCCAGAGCUGUCGCCAUUUCCAAAGCCCAGACUUGGGAACUCAGUACCUGGUUGUGCUGAAUCAGAAGUUCACUGACUGCUUUGUGCUAGUGUUUCUGGACUCCCACUUAGGAAAGACGUCUCUGACAGUGGUUUUCCGAGAGCCCUUCCCAGUACAGCCCCAGGACAGCGAGAGCCCCCCUGCCCAACUGGUCUCCACCUACCACCACCUGGAGUCUGUCAUCAACACAGCCUGUUUCACCCUCUGGACCCGCCUCCUCUGAGGGAGUGGACUGGACCACUGAAUGUCACUGUUCCUUGAAUCAUGGGCCUACCAGAUUGCCUGCCAGAGGCAGGACUGACCAGCCCUUCUGGGCCCCAGGGCAAGCCAGACACUGAGUGACACCAAAGGCUUUGUAACUAUGUCUUGAGGGUCUGCUGCCCCAGCCUGGCAGCAGGAACCGCCCUCCCCAAACACCCACAGCCACUGACCCAUCCAGGACUCCAGAGAGUCAGGUCAACCCCGAGGACCCCUUGGGCCCUUCUGGGGUACUCCUUUCGGCCCCCCUGGUAGAGUCUCGGGAGUUCACACAGGGUGGCAAACACCCCCUAGAGCUCCUCUGCCUGAAUCCUGCCCCCUAGCCUUUGACCACUGUCAGCCACCUGUGUCCCUUGAGCCUUCGGGUCUUCACUUCCCACUUGGACAUCACUGCUGGACAUUCCCAUCGAGAUGACACCUGGGUUCCAAUCCCAGCUCUGCCUUUGAAGCACUUGUGGCCACCGUCAAGUCCCUUUGCUCUCGGACCCUGGGUUUCUCAUCCUUUAAUGAGGUGGGUUCAGAAGCUCUCCCAUCUUCACAGCAACCCUGGCACUGGCUUCUCAAUGGGAGGGAAGCAGCAGAGAAACUGAAGUGUUAGACACUAUGUGUCCCACCACCCCAUUACAGAGACAUAUGACAAUGUUCAGCAGGUCAUCUUUAAUGCAGAGGAGGAGAUGGGAUGUCACUCGCUGUCUGGAGGCACGUGGGUGGUGUGCGGGCCCUCACUGGCCAGCCUCUGGGUGGCCCCGCCUAUCCCAGUAUGAACGUAGCCAACUCAAGCCCUCUACUGUGUCUCCUGCAGGGAGAGGGAGGCCUCGGCACCUCAGCCCACAAGGAGAAAACAGCCCCUGUCCGGGUCCCUCCAGAGCUCCCUUCCCCAGGGCCACGCCUCACCUCGAGGCUGAUACUCACAGCCCACGAAGCCUUUGUAGCCUUCAUCUUCCAGCAGUUGAAACAGAUAGGGGAAAUUCAGCUCUCCGGGGCUGCUGGGCUCCCCUCGGCCUGGGACCUGUGCCACCUGCACAUGCCCUGGGGACAGAUGUGGACAAAUGUGGGGUCCAGGCUCCUGCCAGGGCCUGAAGGACAGAUGUGGGGAUUGAAAGGGUGGGAGGGCAAAGGAAGGUCCUCUCACCAACAAUGGGCAGGAACUCCCGGAUGUUUCCUGUCAGGUUCCCAUCCAUGAUCUGCCAGUGGAAUAUGUCCUAGGGAAGAGGAUACUACAUUCCGAGACCCCGCAGGCCCCGCCCUCCUUCCGAUCUGCGAAGUACCCCCUUCCACUUACCAUUUGUAAUUGGAGGUUGGGUCUUCCUACCUUCUGUAAGAUGGCUGCCGCUGUAAGAGAAGCCAGGGAGGGGACCGUGAGCCUCAAGAGCACAGGAAUCAAAAGGGACAGAAGGAGAGACAGGGCUGGGGUCGUACCCUGCUGGGGCGUGUCCAGGAAGUACUGGGGGUCAGUGAUGCGGGUGUUGAUGGGCUCCAGCAGUCCCACGAGGUCCUCCUAGCAGCAUGUCGGGUGCUGUGAAUAGAGCUCCUUCCCAAGUUUGUCCCCCAUCAGUCAGUCACUGGUCAAGGCCCUCACCUGUUCCUCUGACCUAGGCUGGCAGCCUCACGUGCUGUCCCCACUGUGCACCCCCUUCUCCGCACACCCACAGAGACAUGUAAGUACGUGUGUGUUUCCACCUUUCUCACCUGAGCCAAAACCCCAGCUGCAUGCCUCAGGUUCUCCAGAAAAACGGCCUCCAUCUCAGCCUUGACUGCUAUUCGAUCAGCUCCCUGGGGUACUCGGCCAGCCAUCAGGUGGAUCCUGUGGGGAAGAUGGACUGGAGGCCUUGCCUCCCUUGGCUCUCUCUGCACCUCUUCCAGGAUUCCCUGACUGUGCCAGCCCUCGUCCGUCUCCCCAGGUCUCCAGUCCAUGGCACCUGGGUCACGAUGCCCAGGUAUCCCAGCACUUUCAGAGACACUUCAGUGAUGGCUGAGGGGCAAGCCCUUUCCCAGACAUCUCAGUGUCCACCCACCGCCUCCUGCCUCCAGUACUUUCCAAAACCUUUCCUUCCCUCGGUCCUUCUCCGCAACCUGUAACCUGCUAAAUUCUCACCUUUAAAAAUUGUCCUGACCUUUGCUUGCCCUUCUCAGGUAUUCCAUGCUGCUGUCUCUACUUCCUCUCCUCGCAUCUACUUAGCCUUUUCCCAUCUGUUUUCUGCCCCCACCAUUGACCAGUAGUGAUCCCCUCUUGCCAGUUCCUUCUGAGCCUGUUUGGCCUCUGCAGGAUUUGACAUUUGAAUCAGCCCCACUUUGAGCCGUCCACCUCCUCCCAUCAUCCCCUGAUCUUAGCCACAUCCAGCUCCAAGCAGACAUUCCAGGCCUCCCCAUCCCAACAGGCUACAUACAUGUCCAGCCUCAGGAACGCUGCCAAAUACACCAGGCCUCCUCUUGCCACAGCACCCUUGCAAGGAACACUCAACUUCCUGCCCAUCAAGCAAUGCCCACUCCUUGAAGACAGUCCAAGCAUCACUACCUGUAAGCAGCUUUCUCUGAUCCAGACAGGGUUAGGUGCCUACCCUGCUCCCACAGCUUCCUGGAAUAGGCCUGUCCUCAAAUGCAUCACUGUAUAUAUUUACUCUCCUAUCUGCCUAGGCAGACUGAGCUCCCAGCAUGGGAUCCCAGCAUGGGGUGAGCAUGAAAGAGUGGCAAACAGAGUGGCAUAAGACAGAUAAAAUACAAAAGGCAAUUUACAAAGGACCAGGACCGCAGAGGCAGAGAUAAACCAGUGGGCUCAGACUUCUGAGCGUCUCAGAUCUGGCGUCCUCGACUCCCUGAACCUGCAUCAGGGUCAUGGGUCACAGGGGUGGGGGUGGGGUGGAGCGGGGUACCUGGGACAGCCCAGGGCUUUGGCAUACCGCACGGCCUGCUCCAGUCCCUCUCGGAAGGCCGCCUGUCUCCCGGGGACGGCCCCCAGCCCCAUUUCCCCCUUCUCUUGGUCUCCUGCAGAGAGAACGGGCCUCAGCCCCCGGCUCGGACACUCCCCUGCCCGCGCCCCGGCACCCCCCAGCCCUCCCAGCCCUCCCGGCCCGCGACGCACCCGGGGGCGUGUUGAUCAGUACAAGCCGCAGCCCCGCUUCUCGCGCGGCGCGCGCCAGCGCCUCAGGCGUCUCCGCGUACGGCCAGGCCACCUCGACGGCCUCGAAGCCCGAGCUGCCCGCGGCCCGCACCCGCGCGGGGAGGCCGGAGAGCUCGGGGAAUAGCCAGGACAGAUUGGCGGAGAAGCGCAGCGGCGCCAUGCCUGGGGAGGCCGGGCCGGGCGGAGUCCGCGGGAUCCAAAGGCGGCGGGCGGCGGGCGGCGGGCGGCGGGCGGGGGCGGGGCUCUCCUUGCUGGCCCUGCGAACGAACGAGCACUGUUCGUGGUUAGAAAAGCGAAGUGCUGUAAAAACCCGGGCCUUCACGAAAAGCGCCUACGGUUAGCGAGAGAGGGAUCACGGGGAGAGGCGAAGGGGCGGAGCGAGGGCGGCCGGAAAAGGAGCAGGACCCGCGCCUGGAGAAGGUAGGGAGGCCGAGCUCCAGGGCCUGAGAGCCGGACGCGAAGCAAGAGAGAGCUGGCUGCCCGAGGGCCCGGUUGCAAUGAUGGGACGCGCACUUUAAUACUGAGUCUUUCCUCUGAUUAUAAAAAUGCUAUCUGUUCGUUAAGCAACAUUUGAAAGCUGUAUGACCAAAUAAAGAAGCACUUUUAUACCGCCA